ACUCAUGGGCAUCUCUUCUGUUAAGAGACAUUCCCCACUCUCCAAGUUUCCCUCAAGCCUGAAGCAGCAGAGUGAGUAGUGUUGGAGCAUGUUUUCAUUGCAUGCUUGGGUCAUGUUGAGUGCCCUCCAGUGGAUAUAGUAUAAUGCUUGUGAUUUUUUUUUUUUUAAUUCCAAACAAGUUUAUGUGGGAUAUAUUUAGGAAUAGUUCUGAUGAGGGAGAAUCAACUAAGAAACCUUUGAUUUCUAAAAUAAUUAAUAUCAUUACUGCUAAUUAAAAUACAGGCUUGAGAAAAUGUCUUCUCAGCCAAUAUUUGCAGUAGAAAAGUCGGGAGGUUUUUUAAGGUCACUUUGAGUAGGCAGUUCUGCUUAAAUAUAUCAUAAUGAUAAACCAGAAUCUCAGUAUAGUACUUUAGGAGGUAAAAGAUCAUAAUAUUCAGUUAUAUUGAUGAAUUACAGCAACUGAAAUUCUCAGAAAAAAAUUAAUGAAAAUGUGAAUUGUCAAUUUGUCUAAAAUCAUUCACAGAGUAAAACAUAAGUGCUCAACUUGAUUAUAUUAGGAAAUAGAUAGAAAUAAAGGUAAUUGAGCCAGUGUAUGUGACCUAAAAUAUAAUGCCCUUAGUGACCAUAGGGUUGGUCUCAUUUGUACAUAGUGGUGGGCCAUGAUGAACUGUGUUUUGCCCUUUGAAUUUUUCCUUAAAAAGCUUUCUCUAGGCUCCUAUGUUCAUGGUUUUUCUGUUAGUAAUAUUAUUUUCUGAAAAUCCAUGUUUCAAAUCAGAAUCUAAUUAGCAACAGGAAUGAAGCUUAUUCUAAAUUAGUUUUUGGAAGUUAAACGGUCAGCAUAUGGAAAUUUUUCAGGGUUUAGAUUUUUAAAAAUUUGUUUUUCAGAAUAUGUUGCUGGAAUGAAAACGUUAGCGUAGGGACGGAAAAUGACACUUACCAGUGAUUGCUUUACUUUGCCUGUGGAAUUCAGUGUAAUUUUGUGGAAACAUUGGUAUAUGAUUUUUUACUACUUAAGAAAUGUAUUGCUAUAGUUAGGGUUUUUUUUUUUUUAAAGGCAAGAAUGCCUCAAGUGCUUUAUGUGAAUGAUUAUUUCAGGAUGGAUUAAAUAUUCCUCCAUCAAGGACCAUACUUGUAAAUCAGUGAUUUCCAAGUUGGUGCUUAGUAUUUACAGCAUUUACUGUCUAUAAGCUUCUGUUCUGAUUUUUCAAGAGUUUUCUGAGAAAUGAGAGUAGGCUUAAAAGUUCUUUGAAAAAUUAUGUACAUACAACUUACUGAAAAAAAUUGCUACCGGGGACUUAAUUUGUCUCUUGAAAUGGGCUACUUGCCUUCAUUAAUGUAGCAUACUACAAUUUGAUGUUCAAGAUAUGUUACUAAGAAUAAGAUCGCUUUCAGAAGCCUUAUAUAGGAUUGGUCUUACUACAUUGUAGUGGGAAUGGCUACUCAAAUGUCUCCAGGGCCAGUUAGGUAUUGGGUAAAUGGGACCAUGCAGACUAUUAAAAAUUGAAGUGCACAUGAAGCAGCCAGUCAUAAGCAGCUCCAGCCACUGUGUGGGAAUAUAGUUUAUGUUGCCAGAUCAUCUGAUUUCUUUCCCCUAAGUGGGAAAUCCAGAUCAAUGUACAUCUCUUGAUUUGCAAGUGUUGGUGAACAAAAUUCAUAUUUUAAGAUGCUGUAUUCAGCACAAAUUAAAUACACUUAUUUGCUGAAUACUGCCAGUUUGUCCCUCUGCAGUAGUACCAUUUGAAGUACAGUGUUUUCAUAAUGAUUCUGUGAAAUGACUGGUUCUGUGAAUGUACAUAAUUUAGCAGAUAACAUUGUUAAAUUAUUAGGUUUGUAUUUAUUUAGGCACUUGGGAAAUGCCUUGUGUCAAUUGAUUAUAGAUUAGGAGCUUAAAAGCAAGAUUUAUAUUAUCAACUUAUUUGUGAAGACUGGGAAACCCACAUUUUUAAAGUUAGGAAUUAAGAUGGCCAGGUUCAAGGAAAAGGGGGAGAAGUAACUUUCUUAUUACUCAACCAUCUUAAAUAGAGUUCUUUAAGUGUAUUUUUAAGAGGUCUCAAAACUUAAUCUGAAGGGACGUCAAAUGCUGGACAAAUUCUGUGUAUACAACUCAAGUCAGCCCCCAAUUUUACUGGUCUUUAAAUCAUGUCCUUUUUACCAGAAGUUUGCAUUUCUAAGCUAAACUAUUACUGUUAGACUAGAUCCAAAACUUAAAAACAGUUUAGGUAAUUAAAAAUUAAUUGAAUAUAAACGUUUUACUUAAAUUAAUGGCAAAUGGCUUUUUGGCCAAUUUAAGUUUAUGUAGGCAGUUAAAUCGAUUUUGGUUAAAUCUUUUGCUGCUAACAAGGUAUUUCCAGAUUUUGAAAAGUGGGGUGGCCUGGUGCCUGUAGUACCAGCACUUUGGGAGGCUGGGGAGGGUGGAUCACCUGAGGUCAGGAGUUCGAGACUAGCCUGGCCGACGUGGUGAAUACAAAAAUUAGCCAGGCAUGGUGGCAGGUGCCUGUGAUCCCAGCUGCUUGGAAGUCUGAAGCAUGAGAAUUGCUUGAACCUGGGAAGCGGAGGUUGCAGUGAGCUGAGAUCACGCCACUGCACUCCAGCUGGGGCAACAGAGCGAGACUCCAUCUCAAGAAAGAAAAGUGGGGUGUUUAGUCUUCAAACUCCGUGUUUAAGUGACUGGAGUGAAAAUGUAAAUCAUAGGCCGGUGUUGGUUUAAAAAGCAUCAUCUGAAAAUAAUGCUGUAGUCUGCAAUUAUUUUUAUUACGAUACGAUGGUGUAAAAUACAAGCAGAUCAGUGAACCAUUCAUGAAACAUUAAUCCUAAAGGCGUCUCACCCCAAGUCUAUCCCACAAUCUCCAUGAGACUUCGUGGAACCACUGUAAAGUUUCUUGUGUAAUAUCCCAGAAGUUUCCUACCUCUGGUAUCUUUUGAACUUGUUGAAAAGGCUUUUCCACCCCCUCUUUAUGAUGGUUUGAAGAGUGUGAACAUCUGAAUGAUGCUGGGGUGAAACUGCUUCAUAACACUUCCAUUUUCUCCCCUAUUUAUUUCCAUAUUUUUAUUUUUUCACUAAUAUCCCCACGGUUUUACUUCUGUUUUAGUAAUUCACAUGUUGCUGGACUAAUUCUUUUUAACUGACUUGUAACAGAUAUGUUAAACCGUUUAAAACUUGGGGGGUAUUUUUAACCUACUUUAAGUUAGUUCAAGUUAAUCAGUCUACAUGGCAUAUAAACCUUAUGAUUAAUAAAUCUUAAAUGCUGGUAGCUGAGUUGGAAGCCAAAGACGUACAAAAAAGCUGAAGUGUUAGGUUUAGUGUGAUAAGCUUCUCUUACUAACAGGGUUUUGUAAUAGCAGAAAUAGAUAUAUGCAUAUAUAUGUGCAUAUAUAUAGCAUACCUUAUUGGAUGUCCAUAUAAAAAUGUGUAAGAAGUUAAAUUUACUGCAAAAUUUCUUGGGAGUGCAAUUUGAAGAUGAUCUUAAGUGGUGAUAGUAGUUUGCUACACUGGGGGAUAGUUGUUGCAAACUGCUCCUAAUUUUCCUUUACUGUGAAGUAAACUGAACAGCUGUAAUAGGGAUUAGGAACUGUACUCCCUCUCUCUCUUUUUUAAGUAUAAUUAAGUGGUUUUGGGGUAAGGGUGUAGGGAGUGAGUGUCUUUGAAGUUUUGCAUAUACUAGAUGAAUGCCACAUGUAUAAGGGAGGAACAAGGGAUUCUUGGAAAUAUUUUUCAAUCCAAGUAACUUUGGAGGCUUCCAAGUGGAGUUCAUUCCCCUGUGUAGGAAAGUGCUGGGGUAGACCCUUAAAUUCCUUUCUGAGCCAUUGAAAGAAUGUCCUCAAACUUCGCUUAUACUUUAUAGUUCAUUUAGAUACAAAAGUUACAAACUGAAUGCUAUUUAGGAAACGUAAUACACUGACAUACCGCUCUUUAAAUAGAUUAUAAAUUUAGUAUAUCAAUUUUCUGGCAUUUUGCUGAAUUUUAUUGUUUAGUUUUCAAGCCCAACUAUCUUGUUACUUUGUAUAUCGUAGUUGUCCCCCGUUGAUCACUGUUUCCUGCUUAAUUGUGCUGUCGUUUUUCCUGGGUCCUGAUUCAGAGUGUCAGCAUUCUGUUCCCCAUAGAAUAAGAAGAGGCUAGAAAGUUUACAGAUGAGAUAUCUAGGAAUGCCAGAAGAUCAGGGGUCACCGUUGAGGCAGAGUAAUUAAUUAUGGUUAAAAUGGUGUUGCUGAUAAGUGGGUGCUGGGAAAUAAUUAAAAUUUGAUUUUUUAGAAGAAUACUUCUCAUGCUUGAAGAGCGCCCUCAUUAUAUGCUAAAGGGCCUCAGGUUUUUCCUUAUUGCCAUUAUGCUGCAGAUUCUAUUACAUUUGUCUGAAAAGAUCUAAGACAGAAGGGCUGUUUAAUACCUUCCCUUUUCUCCUGAACUUCCCCUCUCCUCUCCCCCAUCAGGAGCUAAGUAGGAACCCCUUCACCUUGUUACCAUCAGAUUUCAUCAAUGGUCUGUCUUUACAAUGAAGGAAGUAGUACUGCAUUCUGGGCAGAGGCCAGUCCUGAGGCAUGCCUUUUCAAGGACAUUGUUACUUUAGUUACACUGGCUCUUCUGUUUUAACUCUUAUCCCCCAGACUCUAAUCCUGUUGCUUUUUUUGGUCCCCAUCUCCCACCUUUCAUCAUCUGAAAUCCAUUCAUUGUAACUUCUGGAACUCAGUCGUUAGAAAAUCCUUUAUAUUCUCAAUCUUGUGAAUGUUCCUUUCUUUCUUAUUCCAGCUGUAACCUAGCCUUCUCCCCAAGAAUGCUACUUCCCUUGCAGCUCUCUCAAGUGGUGAAUUUUUCCCUUCUUGCACACCUUAUAACACUGAACUAGGAGGUGUGUGGACUAAAUGUCUGCUUUUGUUCCUUAUUGUCACUUCUUGACCUUUAUUUUCCAAAACUUCAAGCUUUGACUUUCAUGUGAUCAAAUUAUACCACCCACUGCCUGUCUUUAUUUCAAGCACCUGCAAACCUUCCUGGGUCAUUCACAUCCUUCUUUGUUCACUUCAUUAGCUCUUGGCUCAUUGUCACUGUCUCUUAUUUCUGUCAUAAUUCUUGGUGACAUCAGUAUCUAUGUAGAGCAAUACUAGUGAAGAUGUGGUCUGGUAACUGUUACCUGUAUGAAUUAAGAUAAGGAGUUAUGCCAGAAUAUAAGUCACCUGUGUCACUAAGUUUACUGUUUAGCUUACUUUUUUUGUAGCAAGAUUUUGAUGAAGGACGCAAUAUGUUGAUUUACAGUCUGGUACAAAUUUUGAUGUAGAAGAUGCUUCCAAUAUCCUGGUCUCUUAGUUCCUUGAUUUCUUCUCCAGUGAUCUUAUUUUCUACCCUAACUCAACUACAUAUUCCCAUUGUCAUAUCCUAGAAUAUUUUGUCUUUUAUCUGUAACUCUGCUCUCUUCCCCCAAUCUCAUUUCAAGCAUCCCACUUUCUAAUUCCUCUAGUAAAUACGUCAGUUCCAACAGCCCAUCAAUCCCAUUGGGACCUACAGUUUAUCUAUCCAAGCUUUUCCCUGUUCCUCACCCUCACUUCUAUACAGCUGAAGUUUCAUACUGAAUUAUAAUCACUUUCUCGUAUACACGUUUAACAAUCUUGUCCCUCCCUGGCUUCAUGCCCAGUGAUCUCUUGUAUCUAUGACCAUGUCCUUUAUCUUCUCCUCUGUCACUGGAUGAACUGUAGCCUUCCAAGAUAAGGCCACUCAGUUCAUUUGUACAGCAGAUUCCAUCCCCUCUUGCUCUCAAGAAUAUUACUGUGGUAUCUCUCUUUUCUUGUCUCUACUGGCUCUUUCCAUGAGCAAACAUGGUAUUAUCCCAUUACAAAAAAAAUUUUUUCUCCGUCUCUCCUUCCACUCACCACCUCAGUCUCUGCUUCUCUUUCCCGCAAAAUAACCUUGAAAAAUUGCUUUAUGUACUCCCGUUUUCUUUUGAACCCCUGCCAGUGACCACCACGUUAUAAAUUUGUAGUUGUCAUCUCACUUAAUCUGUUAGUAGUAUUUGGCACCAUUGCUACAGUUGCUUGAAAUGCCUUUUCAUUGGUUUCCAGGCCACCAUGUCUGUUAGCAGCUUUUCCUCUUACUUCACUAGCAUUUCCUUCUUUGUUUUUUCUGUUAUCUUUCUGACCUCUGUUGGAGUGGCUGAAGGUUUAGUCCUUGAAUCUUUUUUUGUUGUGCAUAUUUACUCCAGUAUCAUAGCUUUAUACAGAUGGUAUUUACAUCUGUUUGCUAACGAUUUCCAAAUUGGUAUCCUUAAACUGGUAUCCAGCUAUUUUUUGGUCAGCAUUUUGGAUGUCUAAGAAGCUUCUCAAACUAAACUGACCUCCCGGUUUUCCCCAAAGCUGCAUCUUAGUCUUUUCCGAAAUGCAAUUCUGUCUUUCCAGUUACCUAGCUUAAAAGCUUGCAGUUCUUGACUCAUCUUUCUCUCAUACCACGUAUCUGAAUUCUCUCUGCAAAAAAUUGUCUGUUCUCCCUUCAGAAUAAAGUCACGUGUCAUUUUAUGAUGGGGAUACAUUCAGAAAUGCGUCAUUAGGAGAUAAUCAUGGUUGUGUGAACAUCAGAGUAUACAUAGACAAACCUAGAUGGUAUAGCCUACUACACAUCUAGGCUAUAUGGUGUGGCCAAUUACUAUGAUGAAUACUGUAGGUAAUUGUAACAUAAAGGUAGGUAUUUUUAUCUAAACGUAUUGAAACAUAGAAAAAGUACAGUAAAAAAUAUGGUAUCAAAAAUAAAAAAUGGUACAACUGUAUAAGGCAGUUGUGAUGAAUGGAGCUUGCAGGAUAUGUUGCUCUGGGUGAGUCAGCGAGUGACGAUUGAGGGAACGUGAAAGAUGUGGGACAUCACUGUACACUACUGUAGACUUUAUAAACACUGUACACUUGGGCUACACUACAUUUUUGUAAGGUUUUAAAAGACUUUUUUCUAUAAUAAACCUUAAAUUACUGUCACUUUUUUACUUUAUGAAUUCUUAAUUUUUUAAACGUUUUCACUCUUGUAAUAACACGUAGCUUAAAACAUACAUUGUACAGCUGUACAAAAAUUUUCUUUAUAUCUUUAUAAGCUUUUUUAUAUUUUUAAAAUUACUUUUUACCUUUUAGCUUUUUUGUUGAAAAACUAAGACAUGGGCCAGGCGCGGUGGCUCACGCCUGUAAUCCCAGCACUUUGGGAGGCUGAGGCAGGCGGAUCACGAGGUCAGGAGAUAAGAGACCAUCCUGGCUAACAUGGUGAAACCCCGUCUCUACUAAAAAUACAAAAAAUUAGCCGGGCGUGGUGGCGGGCACCUGUAGUCCGAGCUACUUGGGAGGCUGAGGCAGGAGAAUGGCGUGAACCCAGGAGGCGGAGUUUGCAGUGAGCCGAGAUAGCGCCACUGCACUCCAGUCUGGGCGACAGAGCGGAAACUCCGUCUCAAAAAAAAACAAACAAAAAACUAAGACAUGAACACAUUAGCCUAGGCCUACAGAGGGUCAGGAUCAUCAGUAUCACUGUAUUUCCAUCUCCACAUCUUGUCCUUCUGGAAUGUCUUCAGAGGCAGUAAACAUAAAUGGAGCUGCCACCUCCUGUGAUAACAGUGCCUUCUGGAAUACCUCUUGAAGGACCUACCUGUGGCUGUUUUAUAGUUAACUUUUUUUUUUUAAGAAGUAACAGAAGGAGUACACUCUAAUGAUAAAAAGUAUAGUAAGUACAUAAACCUGUAACAAUCAUUAUCAUUAUCAAGUGUCAUGUACUGGACAUAACUGUAUAUGCUAUACUUUUUUUUUUUGAGAUGGCAUCUCACUCUGUCACCCAGGCUGGAGUGCAGUGGUGCGAGGAUAGCUCACUGUAACCUCAGACUCCUGGGCUCAAGUGAUCCUCCUACCUCAGCCUCCCAAGUAGCUGGGACUACACCAGGCACCCCACCAUGCCUGGCUAAUUAAAAAAAAUUUUUUGUAGAGACAGGGUCUCACUCUGUUGCCAGGGCUGGCCUUGAAUUCCUGGCAUCAAGUAAUCCUCCCACUUUGGCCUCACAAAGUGCGAGGAUUACAGGUAAGAGCCACCAUGUCUGGCCCACUGUACUUUUAUACAACUGAAGCACAGUAAACCUACUGUGGUUUCGUUUACACCAGCAUCACCACAAACACCAUGAGUAGAACAUUGUGCUGCGACGUUAACGAUGGCUACAACAUCACUAGGUGAUAGGAAUUUUUCAGCUCCAUUAUAAUCUUAUGAGACCACUGUUGUAUGUGCAGUUCAUCAUCCACUGAAAUGUCCUUAUGUGAUGCAUGUCUUCAUAUCCAAAAAUAUUAAUCAUUUCUCACUGAAGCCAUGCCAUGCCAUGCCAUCUUUUGCCUGUAUUAUUAUUUUUCAGCUUUUAUUUUAGAUUCAGGGUGUACAUGUGCAGGUUUGUUAGAAAGAGUAUAUCGUAUGAUGCUGAAGUUUGGGAUACAGUUGAACCAGUCACCCAGGUAGUGAGCAUAGUACUCAAUAGAUAACGUUCUAACAUUACUCCUCCUUCCCUCCCUGUUCUUGUCUCUGUCUAUUGUAUCUUUAUGUCCAUGUGUACCAAAUGUUUAGCUCAUUCUUGUGAGAACAUGUGGCAUUUGAUUUUGUUUCUGUGUUAAUUUGCUUACAAUAAAUAGUCUCCAGCUGCAUCCACAUUGCUACAAAGGACAUGAUUUUGUUCUUUUUUAUAGGCUGCAUCAUAUUCCAUGGUGUAUAGGUACCACAUUUUCUUGAUCCAGUCUACCGUUCAUGGGCAUUUGGGUUGAUUGUAUCUUUGCUAUUAUGGAUGGCUUUUGCCUAUAUUAUUGGAAAGGCCUUCUAACUGGUGUCCCUGCUUACACCGUUUUCCCCCUUAAAUGUGUUUUCAACAUGGUAGCCAGAGUAACCCUUUUUAUAACAAUAAAUCGUGUAACUUUUUUGUUCAGAAACUUACAGGGCUUACCAUUUCAUUCAGUAAAAGCUCAAGCUCCUGUAUAGUCAGACCAUAUCCUUCAUCACCUGUUACUUUUCUCCUCUGACUCUUCAGCCUUUUUGUUUUUCCUCAAACUGAUGAAGCCUUCAUGGCUGAUGUCAGAUGUUUUGCCCAUUGAGAUCUUCCUUGUUGACUCAGUUGCACUUGGUCAUAUGAUUUUCAUUUAUUUGGGGUAUCUAAUCAUAAUCUGAAAGUUGGCUACUUAUUUUUACCCCUUUGAGGGUCCUUGCCCUGUUUUUGUAUCCCUGAUAGCGGGACAGCCAGAUAUCUGGAACUUACAGGUGUUCAAUAAAGUUUUGUUGAAUGAAUAUUCUGGAAUCACCCAACCUUUUUUUUCCCCUCCACUUAUUUUUCUUCUCCCUUUCACGGCCUGAAAGAUGUCCUAUGUAUAUGGUUCCACUUAUCACUCUCAUCCCAGUUUGUGAUAUACUAUUCCAUUAUAUUACUAUUAUUAAUACAAUUCCAUUGAACUUGCUCUUGCUGACUUCACCACUGGACCUACAUGUUGGCCAAAUGGAUACUUUAUAAUUUUAGUCUUGACCCCUGCCUUUGGCACAUUUCUUACCUCUAGCACAGCACUGUCCAGUAAUCCACACUUUCUGAGACAGUGGAAAUGUUCAGUAUCUGUGCUGUUCAGUUGGUAGCAACCAGCUACCCAUGCCUAUUAAACAUUUGAAAUGUGGCUGUGUGACUAGUGGCAAUUAUGUUGGAGAGUACAGUUUUAGAAACUCCUGUUUUUCUUACAUGGCACUACAUUUAGUAUCACAAUCUAAUUGUGCAAGCCAGAUAGGUAGGAGUCAUCUUUAUUCCUGUUAUUUAAUUUUUCUCAUCUACUAUAUCCAGUUCAUCACAUCAACAGCGCCUGUUGUUUCUACCUCCUAAAUAUUUCUUUAGUCUAACUACUACUUGUCCCUAGUGCCACCACCAUCUAUCAGCUGGAAUAUUGCUAUAGCUGCCUUACAGGUUUCCCUUCUUUCCUGUUCUCUUCUAGUUUUUUGAAUUUUAGUCAGCACGAGAUUUUAAAAACUCAAAUAAGAUUGUGUUAUUCACCUGCUUAAAACCUUUCAUGACUUUCAGUGUCACGUAGAACAGAAAACACUUUUCUUACCAAAGGCUAGAGAGCUCUACGUGAUCUGGCUAUUUUUAACGUUUCAUUGCACUCACCCUUUUCCUCUAUAAUCAAACUACUCUGAUCUCAAGGGUUAGUUCUUGAAAGAUGAUCAUGUUCUUUAAUGACUUUAGGUUUUUGUGUGUUAUUUUCUAUUUCUGGGAUGUUUAUUCUCUGUUCCUUACAUGCUGGCCCUUUUGCAUCCUUCUUCAGGUCUCAGCUUACAUGUUACCUUCAAGAAGCCUUUGACCACUCUAAGUGGGCCCUUCCUUCCACUUCUGCUGUGUAAUCCCACUCCCUUCUCCCACUUGUUAAUUAGUUACAUACUUUUUUGUAAUUGUUUAUUUGGUUGCUGUCUCCCUCUCAAGAAUGCAGGGACCAUGUCUGCAUUCUGCAGUAAUCACUACUGCACACCCAGAAUCUAUUACAGAUCCUGGCAUGUAGCUGAUGCAUAAAUAUUUGUUGAAUGAAAGUCUGUACAUUGUAUUUAUGCUAUUGGUAUUGCUAUGACCUGAAACUAAAAGGAGUUGUGGAAAAGAUUUCUUAUGGAACAGAAAUAUCCCUUUUGAUUAAUAUCACAAUCUCGUAAAUUGAGAAAACAAAAAAAUAUAUACUACUGGAGCAUUCAUGUAUAGUUGGAGAUUAUGACUCAUUUAUUGGUGUGUUUUUGGACUCAGAACAAAGAUGAGGGAAUAUUCCUUAAAGCUCUGUAUUGAAAUAACGAAAAGCAGUCACAUUUUAAUAAUAGAAGCUUCCUAGCUUACUCUUUCUGUAAUCUUCUUUUCCUAAAUGUAAGAGAGCCUCAUAAUUAUGAGGCUUAUUACUAGAGUAAGGCUGUCAAAGGCAGCAAAAUGUCUUUCUGUUUGGAAGAAUAACAUAAACUUGACAUGUAUGGUGGGGGACAGAAGGUUUCAAAAGUUUAAGAAUCUGUGUUGUCUUAACAAAUAGAUGCUUCUCAAGGAGCUUACGCUAGUGGUUACUCUGUCCAGUCAGGGUUUUUUCUUCUUUAACUUGGGUUCAUUUCCUGAUGGCACACAUGAAGUUUGGAUCAUAUGGUUUGACUUUAGCUAUGGUCCUUAGCUAUGGGGAGCAGCAUCAGCGACCUGUGACAUGUAAAUUAAAAAUACAAUGCCAGGGCCCUUCCCCAGCCCCUCUGAUAGAGAACCUCUUGGCCAUCUGUAUUUUUAGAUGUUCCAGGUUAGUCUGAUUAACACCCUUGGUUAAGAACCAUUGGGAGGAUCUGAUUGCCAGUUUAAGGGGACCUUCAAGCCUGUAGGUCUUUAUAGUUAAAAAAAAAAAAAGAUUUUAAAAAUCAUGCAUAUGUUGUGGCUGAAUUCUGGUUUAGCACAUACUGCUUUUAAUGGCCUGAAAUGUUUUUCCCAAAUAAAUUGUCUUGUUAUAGCUUUCAUGUGUGAUUUGGUCCAGCUUCUUGUUUUGAAGAUACUUACGGGGGGGAACACUUUGUGAUUUCUCUUAGUAACAUAUUAACCCACUUAAAAACCCUUUCUAUUACAGGUCUUCACAUUUAGGCUUAAUGUGCUUAAUUCAAAUGUAAAAAUACACCUGCCUUUGUUCUCAGUGAAAGUAUGUAAUAAAUAAAUGAGGGGUUGGCAAACUACUGCCCACCAUCUGUUUUUUUAUGGCCUAUGAACUAAGAAUCGUUUUGGAUAGCUAAAAAAAAAAAUCAAAAGGAUAAUUAUUUUGUGACGUGAAAAUUAUAUGAAAUUCAAAUUUCAGUUUCUGUGAAUGAAGUUUUAAUGGAACACAGCCAUCCAUGCUUAUGUAAGUGUGCAUAUUCUCUGGCUGUUUUCACUGCAAUAGCAGAGUUGAGUAGUUGUGACAAAGAGUUUAUGGCCCACAAAACCUAAAAUAUUUACUUUCUGAUGCUUUACAGAAAAAGUUUCCUGAACCUUAUUCUAGCUAUAUGUUGUUCAUAAAUGAAUCUUUCGUGGUUCUGAAGGCAUUUAAGAAUCUCUUAGGUUAUAAAUUGGCUGGGCGCAGUGGCUCACGCCUGUAAUCCCAGCACUUUGGGAGGCCGAGGCUGGUGGAUCACGAGGGCAGGAGUUCAAGAUCAGCCUAGCCAAGAUGGUGAAACCCUGUCUCCAUUAAAAAAAAAAAAAAAAAAAAAAAAAUAGCUGGGGUUGGUGGUGGGCAGUAAUCCCAGCUACUCGGGAGGCUGAGGCAGAGAAUUGCUUAAACCCAGGAGGCGGAGGAUGCAGUGAGCCAAGAUCGCGCCACUGCACUCCAGCCUGGGCAACAGAGUGAAACACCAUCUCAAAAAAAAAAAAAAAAAAAAAACACUCUUAGGUUAUAAAUAAUUGUUGUUAGCUCUCCAAGCCUCCAUAUUACAUUUUGUGUGUUCUCCUGUUCACAUUUUGAGCAUUUUAUUUUUUAUUAGCACAUUCAGUUCAUCAGGUAUUUAAGAGCUUAAUAUAUGCCAAAGCAUAUAUUAAGCGAGAAGCUGUUUCUAAAUGUACUGUCUCAGCCCUCACAGAGUUCACUUCAUUAGGCUCUUUAAAAUUUCUUUCUUUAAAAGGUCAGCGUGCUGGUAUAGUGGGGAAGGGAAACUCUUACAACACGUCGAGUAGAGGAAGGUUAUCAUUAUGGGAUAUAAUUUGGAAGUCAUUGAGUACCUGCCAUUAAUUCUGCCUGUAGUCUGAAUGUAGAGAUUAACAUGUAGAAACUUUUUUGAAAUAAAAUCUUCAAUUUCUUUGGCAUAUCUAGUACUGUCUAGCUAGGCAUAUAGUCAAAGUAUGGUGUAUAUUUCAAGUAUUAAAAGUUUUUUUGGGCUGUAGUCACUGUUGAAAGGAUAUAGUUCUUUACUAUUACAUGUGAUACCUUUAUAUAAAAUUGGCUAACCCCUGUCUUUCAUUUAUCUGCAACACUGACUGUUACCAGUUGUCUCUAACUUUGGUAUGGGGGGUGGAAAUAUGAUUAGAUUGAAAGGGUACAUGACUGAGCCACAAGCAGACCUGGAUUUGAAUUUUAACUGAACGGUUUAUUAGCUAUUCUUACAUUAAUACUGCUAAUCAGUUUUCUUGUGAUAUGAGGAAUGAUGUCUUCUUUAUGAGGUUGCUAGGAAGAUUCAAUGAGAUAACAUACUAGGCUCAGAACUGAAGUUGCUAGGAAUUUAAUUAUGCUACCUUGUUAAAGUAUGUCAAAGGCAGAAUUCAGUGUUUAGCUGAUACCACAAGGCAGUAUCCUAAAAUUAUGCUGUAAAAGAUAUAAAGAUGCUGUAAGUGACUCAGAAACCUAGUGACUUUGUAAUGCAGUUGAUUCUUAGAAUACUGUCACUUUAACAGAAUAGGAGCUAGGAAUGAAGAAAUAGUUAUUAAAUUACUAAAAUAGAAAAUUUAUUGACACAUGUAAAGUGACAUUUGCUUAAAUAUUGAAAAAUUUGUAGUACUAUUUCCUUGCUUUAGAAAACAUUGGUUACCACUUUUUUUAUUUAUAGCAGUUUGUUUUUGCCUUGAGGCAAGAUGGUUGACUGAGUAGUUGCCACAUUUCUUUUGUACAAAGUCCAUUUCAUAGGCCAUCUAGCUUUUAUGCUUAGAAACAUUUCCUUAACGUUAUAUUUCAGUAUUUGGCUAACCUAUAUAGGGUUAAAUUAUAUAGGCUAACUUCUCGGACAGAUAUUUCUAAUAAUUUAUGUAUUUGGUUCUGCAAAUGUAUGCAAAAAUAUAUGUACAAAGGUAUGCAGAUGCCUUGCAUACUUGAUAUAUGUUAAAUUUUUUUUAAUGUAGACCUUUUUCGUUCUCUUUAAUGACUAUAUGGUAUUCCACCAUCCCCCGCUCACCUGGACAACUACAGUAACCUCCUAAAUGGUGUUUCUACUUUGCUAUUGCCCCUUAUUGUCUUUUUUCCCCUUUAUAGCUGCUGGAGUGAAUUUUAGAAAGCCUAAGUCAUACAUCACAUUGCUUCAUGGGCAUCCCAGUACACUUUGGAUUUUAUUUUACAUCCUUACUGAUCUGAUUCUCAUCUCUGUCUCUUCAUGGUUCUCUGCCUUCUAGUUACACUGGUGACCUUUCAAAACCUUUACCACAUUGAGUUCAUUCCUUACUUUUCACUCUUUCUCUGCCUGGAGUGUUCUGCCCCAUCUUUACGUGGCCAGCUGCUCCUCCUCUGAUGAAAUGUCUCUUCCUCACAGGCCUUCCCUGACCACCCACUAGAGUAGCACAUCUUCUACCUCAUAAACUUGUUUAUUAGUAUUUCUUACUCUAAAUUUUCUUUUAAAUUGCUUAAUUCCCUAACAGUAGAAUAUAAGCUUCACUGUAUGUAUGAUCUUGUUGACUCUCUUACUCAUUGUUAUUGUAAUACCAGUAACAAAGGGUGUUUAAAAUUUGUUCAGUGGGUGAAUAUAUGUUCCAUUUAAUGGAUAAAUUAUUUUUUAUUCAGUCUCCUGUUGAUGGACAUUUGAAUAAUUUCCAUCUUUUUCUCUAUGAAUGCCUCACUUGGCAUGCUUCUGACAGUAUUGCCACAGAAUACAUUUCUGUUAUAAAAAUUGAAUUUUUAAGUCAAAGGGUAGUUACACUUUAAUGGAUAGUGGCAGCUUACUAUCAAAAGUUUCUGCUAGUUUCACCAUAUCCUUAUUAGCAGUAGAUAUUAUCAAUCUUUUCAAUCUUUGCCAAUCUGAUAAGCAAAAAGUAAAUGGGUUUAAACAUCCUUUGUAUAUAUUCAUUGCUCACUUUAUGUUUUUCCUUUGAAAUGUUAUUUCUUGUUCUUUCCCUGCAGUAUGAUUCUUUCUUUUUUUGACUUGUUCCCAGUUUUUUGUGUACUAUGGAUAUUAGCCUUUAAUUAUGUUACGGAUGUUCUAGUAUGUUAUUUUUUGAAUUACUUCAAAUGUGAUUUGUUGCUCAGAUUUUAAAAACUACAUACACAAAUUAUCUCAUGUUUCCCUUUUUGGUUUCAAUUUCGACUCAUGCUUAAUCAGUUCAUCGAUUGGGCAUGGUUUUAUUCUUAAUAUAUACCCGUAUUUUAUCUCAUUUUAUUUUUUUACGUGUAAAUAUUUGGUGAAUAUAGGUUUAAUUUUAAUGUAAAAUAAGGAUGAAAAAUGAUAGUUGGAAUUACAAGCCCAUUUCUCCUAAUACUUUUAAUCAAGUAAUCCACUAAUUGAAAUAUUACCUUCUUCAUUUAUGAAAUUGCCACAUUAUAUCUGGGUGUUUUUCUGCCUACUACAGUCUCUUACCCAUUUCUUUCCUAAUAAUACAAUACUUGAAUUGCUGUGGUUGUUGAUUUAUAAUGUUAUCUUAAUGAUAACAUUAUAAAUGUGAUGGAACUGGUUCCUCCUUAUAGUUCUUCUUAAAUCAAGAACAAGACAUAUCUUCCCAUUUACUCUCGUAUGUAUCUCAUUUUACUGUUAUGAAUGAAAUCUGUCCUAUUUGUGUAUAGGAAAAUAGUUUUUGUAUGUAAUUGUGAUAUGGCCAGUUUUAUUAAAAAUUUGGUUAAACUAAGAGUUGUUUUCUGUUCAGCCUUAUCAUACUAUAAAAUCCACAUAAAAUGGGUAUAAAAGUGUCGCAGGACACUGGGCUCAGAUGAUUCUCCCACCUCAGCUUCCCAAGUAGCUGGGACUACAGCGGCAUAUGCCACCACACCCAGCCAAUUUUUAAAUAAGUUUUAAAAAUAGUAUUUUUAGUAGAGACAGGGUUUCACCAUGUUGCCCAGGCUGGUCUUGAACUCCUGGACUCAGACAAUCCACCUGCCUUGGCUUCCCAAAGUGUUGGGAUUACAGGUGUGAGCCACCACACCUUGCCGAAUUGCAGCCAUAUUUAAUACUUUUUUCCAUCCUAUUCCCUUUGCUGCCCCCAGGCCUCCUGUAUUGAUAGCCCGCUAUUAAGAAGCUAGUGUAUAUUCUUUGCAUACUUUUACUUCAUAAACUAUAUGAAGCAUUGUUCUGUUUUUUAACUUAAUUGGUAUAAAAUUAUAUUUUGGAAAUUCAGUAUAUUCUGUGAAAAUUAUUUAGAAAAUGUGCCUCUGAGAUAAAGCCUAUUCAGGAUGUAUCUUAAAGGAGAUAGCUGUGCUUUAACAUUAUCAGUCUUUUUGGCUGCUUAUGUUAAUAUAAGUUGGAGAAAAACAGUCUGCUUUUUGUGAUAAUAUGUUCUUGGAGAUGGAGUGAAAGAUUGUUUAAAAACAUUGUCUUUUUUUUCCCCUGAAGUACCAGUAUUUAUUUUAGGAUUAUGUUACUGAUCAAAGAUGCUGUGUGGAGUUACUCAUUGGUGAGACUAACAAUAAAUCACACAUGCAAAGGAUGUUACCAUAAUCUAAUUAUUUUAAACAGUAAAAUUAUAUUCUAAGACAUCCAGUUGGCCUAUAUGUGCUAUAUCAAUGACUAUCAAGGGGCUUUUUAUGUAUACUGUAUACAUGUACUUCACAAAAAUAUAAAAGGAUGACAUCAAAAAUCUGGCAAGCCAAAAGCCUACAUUACAUGUAGCAAAUAAAUAAGCAUAUGAACUUAUUGGAAUUUAAAACCCUGUAGGAUGGGCGGGUGAUGGUAUGUAUGUUAGAUGUGUGGACAUAUCUAUUAAAAGUUGUGUCAGAUAACAGCUGGUGCUGACAAGCCCUUGGUAAGAUGGCAGCAUGUUCAAUAUGUUCUGUGAAAAUUAUCUCAGUUUAUGAUCUGUCAGUAUUGUGGAGCUAUGCAUGAAAGGACUUAAAAUUCUUACCCUUAAACUCAGUAACAGUGUUUCUAGAACUUCUGGUGAUAUGGGAAAUUAAGAGAAUUAUUUAUAUGCAAAGGUGUUUAUUGCAGCAUUGUUGGAAUAAUAGACAAAAUGGGGAAGAACAAGCUCAGAAUGGAGGAGGUAGCUUAUAGUAUAGACAUACGAUACAAUCCAGAUGAUAAUAUUUUAUAAUAGUCUUCACAAGGAAUUUUAUAUUUUUAUUUUUAAAAAUACAUAGCAGUGAGUUUAAUAUACCAAACAUACCAAAAUGUCAUCAUUUACUGUGUGGUGGACUCAUAUGAUGGAGAUGAUAAAUAAAAAUAUUAAUUUAUUUGAGGCAUAUAUUUAUGGCUGAGGAAGGAAGACAGUUAUGAAGAACAGCUCAUUCUGGAAACAUACUAAUUUUUCCCAGCCAUAAAGAGAUUUCCUAUUUCUUUUUUUUUUCCAUUUACCUUCUGUUUCCUACCUGAGAAGAUUUCAUACUUCUAAUAACCAUUUGUGUACCUAUUUAAAGACAGUACCAAAGGCAUACAUUUUAGUGUUUGGAGGACCAAGGGUCAUUUGAUGUUUGAUGCUUAUUGACUAUUCGAGGAUGACAAGACACCUUGAGAACACACACACCCACACCCACACCCACACCCUCACCCACCCACCCCACCCCCCUCCCCGAAGAAAGCUGUGAAGGAAGAAAGCAGAAAAGAACCUGGAGUGAGUUGUAACUUAAAAUGUUAGUGUUGCAUGAAGUGUGUUAAAACAGGAAGAUUUGAGGAAAUUGCAUACAUUUUCUAGAUGGCAAAGUAUUACUGGUGACAGUUAAUGAAAAUGCAUAUGCAUGUGUUUUUAGAUUUACAAAUUUUACUAAGAACUUUUUAAAAAUCCCUGAAGGUGUAUCAAAAGUUUAUCAUGCUUAUGAAAUAGAGUAGCACUUUCUAACUUUAAAACGGGGAAUAAUUCUUUGGAUCUUGAUUAUUGGAAAAGUGAAUUAUGAAUUGCUAGUAUAAAACUGUGGUUUUAAAAUAUGUCUGCUUUAUAUUUUUAUGUAGCAGAUUUACUCCUAGUUAAUAAUACUCAAACUUACUGAAAACUAAGGUAAUUAAGAUAAUUCUGUCCUGAUGGGAAGAGGAAAAAUAACUUCAGUGUGAAAUCUAUUAUAUAUUAGUUGUGGCAAGAUUUCUCCCAUUGACUUUGACUGGAGACAUUUAUAGGGUUAAAAUCGGAAAUAGCACGGUGAAUUUUGAAGUAUCCUUGUAGUUGGAAAGAGUAUUAUGUUCAUAUUGCCAAAAAAAAGAUGCAUGGAUGCAUUAGACUGGAUGGAAAAUACAUGAGAAGUUGGCUAGCCCCCUCUUUGUCAAAACAUCACUUGGUGGUGAUAAAGCUGUUGGAAAACACAGCAUUCUAAUGUAGUCUGUAGUUUAAUGAUAAUCUGUGUCUUGAAACAUUUAGCGUAGUACUUAUACAAACCUAGAUGGCAUAGUGUACUGCAUGCCUAGCCUAUAUAGUAUAGCCUGUUGCUUCUAGGGUGUAAAGCUGUAUAGCGUGUUACUAUAGGCAGUUGAAACAGUGGUAUUUAUGUAUCCUUUUUUUUUUUUUUAAAUUCUUUUAAGAGACAGGGUCUUGCUCUGUUGCCCAGGCUGGAUGCAUUGGUGUGAUCAUAGCUCACUAUAACCUUGAACUCCUAAGUGAUCCUCUUUGCCUCAGCCUCCCCAGUGGCUAGGACUACAGGCACAUACUACCACACCUGGCUAAUUUUUAACAUUUUUUUGUAGAGAUGGAAUUUCGCUGUGUUGUCCAGGCUGGUCUUGGAACUCUUGUGCUGCAGCAAUCCACCCGCCUCCCAAAGUGUUAGAAUUACAAGCCACUUCGCCUGGCUUGUUUACCUAAACAUAGAAAAGAUCCAGUAAAAAUACAGAAUUAAAAUCUUGUGGGGCCACUGUAGCAUAUGUAGUCCAUCUUGACUGAAAUGUCCUUAUGCAGUGCAUGAUUGUACUUCAUAAUUUUUAAGCACUCCUCCCUCUUGAUUGGUACUUAGUGGAUUUUAUCAUUUUUGUUUCUUCAUAAUUCUUUCUGAAAUGUCUACUGGUUGGACCUUUGAUCUCCUGAAUUGAUCGUGAUUUCUUCUGUUGUAUUUUUUGUCUUUGUCAUUUUUUUGUACUCUAGGCAGUUUUCUCAAUUUUAGUUUCUAUUCAACUUUUUGUUUUUAUUUAUUCUCUCCAGUAUUUAUGGAGAUACUAAAUUGAAGUGUUCUGUUUCUCUCUCCACCCUAUCCCUAGUUUCAAGUUUUAUCUCAGUUUCUAUGGAGUCAGUUUUUUCGUUGCUUUAAAAAAAAAUUUUCCUGAAGUGAUUGGUAAGUUUUGGCUAAUUGGGAGCACUAGAAUUGGGCCCUUAAUGGUUGGCAGGGUGUGGUGGAGGAGAGACAGCCCUUAGUCCAAAGGCUCAGGCCAGAAAAAGAAAGAGGAAGGCUUUCCUUUUCCUUUCCGGAGCAGGGUUCUGCCCUAGGUCUUGCUUGGCAGUCUAUUUGAUUUCUUUAGCAGUUAAUGCUCAGUUUUUUGGCAUAUGUGGAUCUGCCUCCAGAGCAGGUACAAGGGUAUUUGAAGUAUACCAUACAACUGUUUUGAAAAUCCAGCGUGGACAAUGGCUACUCAAGGCUACCUUUUGCUCCAUUUUCUGCUCACUCCUCCUAAUGGCUUGGUGAAAUAGCAAACAAGCCACCAGCAGGAAUCUAGUCUGGAUGACUGCUUCUGGAGCCUGGAUGCAGUACCAUUCUUCCACUGAUUCACUGAUUUGAUGGAGUUGGACAUGGCCAUGGAACCAGACAGAAAAGCGGCUGUUAGUCACUGGCAGCAACAGUCUUACCUGGACUCUGGAAUCCAUUCUGGUGCCACUACCACAGCUCCUUCUCUGAGUGGUAAAGGCAAUCCUGAGGAAGAGGAUGUGGAUACCUCCCAAGUCCUGUAUGAGUGGGAACAGGGAUUUUCUCAGUCCUUCACUCAAGAACAAGUAGCUGAUAUUGAUGGACAGUAUGCAAUGACUCGAGCUCAGAGGGUACGAGCUGCUAUGUUCCCUGAGACAUUAGAUGAGGGCAUGCAGAUCCCAUCUACACAGUUUGAUGCUGCUCAUCCCACUAAUGUCCAGCGUUUGGCUGAACCAUCACAGAUGCUGAAACAUGCAGUUGUAAACUUGAUUAACUAUCAAGAUGAUGCAGAACUUGCCACACGUGCAAUCCCUGAACUGACAAAACUGCUAAAUGACGAGGACCAGGUGGUGGUUAAUAAGGCUGCAGUUAUGGUCCAUCAGCUUUCUAAAAAGGAAGCUUCCAGACACGCUAUCAUGCGUUCUCCUCAGAUGGUGUCUGCUAUUGUACGUACCAUGCAGAAUACAAAUGAUGUAGAAACAGCUCGUUGUACCGCUGGGACCUUGCAUAACCUUUCCCAUCAUCGUGAGGGCUUACUGGCCAUCUUUAAGUCUGGAGGCAUUCCUGCCCUGGUGAAAAUGCUUGGUUCACCAGUGGAUUCUGUGUUGUUUUAUGCCAUUACAACUCUCCACAACCUUUUAUUACAUCAAGAAGGAGCUAAAAUGGCAGUGCGUUUAGCUGGUGGGCUGCAGAAAAUGGUUGCCUUGCUCAACAAAACAAAUGUUAAAUUCUUGGCUAUUACGACAGACUGCCUUCAAAUUUUAGCUUAUGGCAACCAAGAAAGCAAGCUCAUCAUACUGGCUAGUGGUGGACCCCAAGCUUUAGUAAAUAUAAUGAGGACCUAUACUUACGAAAAACUACUGUGGACCACAAGCAGAGUGCUGAAGGUGCUAUCUGUCUGCUCUAGUAAUAAGCCGGCUAUUGUAGAAGCUGGUGGAAUGCAAGCUUUAGGACUUCACCUGACAGAUCCAAGUCAACGUCUUGUUCAGAACUGUCUUUGGACUCUCAGGAAUCUUUCAGAUGCUGCAACUAAACAGGAAGGGAUGGAAGGUCUCCUUGGGACUCUUGUUCAGCUUCUGGGUUCAGAUGAUAUAAAUGUGGUCACCUGUGCAGCUGGAAUUCUUUCUAACCUCACUUGCAAUAAUUAUAAGAACAAGAUGAUGGUCUGCCAAGUGGGUGGUAUAGAGGCUCUUGUGCGUACUGUCCUUCGGGCUGGUGACAGGGAAGACAUCACUGAGCCUGCCAUCUGUGCUCUUCGUCAUCUGACCAGCCGACACCAAGAAGCAGAGAUGGCCCAGAAUGCAGUUCGCCUUCACUAUGGACUACCAGUUGUGGUUAAGCUCUUACACCCACCAUCCCACUGGCCUCUGAUAAAGGCUACUGUUGGAUUGAUUCGAAAUCUUGCCCUUUGUCCCGCAAAUCAUGCACCUUUGCGUGAGCAGGGUGCCAUUCCACGACUAGUUCAGUUGCUUGUUCGUGCACAUCAGGAUACCCAGCGCCGUACGUCCAUGGGUGGGACACAGCAGCAAUUUGUGGAGGGGGUCCGCAUGGAAGAAAUAGUUGAAGGUUGUACCGGAGCCCUUCACAUCCUAGCUCGGGAUGUUCACAACCGAAUUGUUAUCAGAGGACUAAAUACCAUUCCAUUGUUUGUGCAGCUGCUUUAUUCUCCCAUUGAAAACAUCCAAAGAGUAGCUGCAGGGGUCCUCUGUGAACUUGCUCAGGACAAGGAAGCUGCAGAAGCUAUUGAAGCUGAGGGAGCCACAGCUCCUCUGACAGAGUUACUUCACUCUAGGAAUGAAGGUGUGGCGACAUAUGCAGCUGCUGUUUUGUUCCGAAUGUCUGAGGACAAGCCACAAGAUUACAAGAAACGGCUUUCAGUUGAGCUGACCAGCUCUCUCUUCAGAACAGAGCCAAUGGCUUGGAAUGAGACUGCUGAUCUUGGACUUGAUAUUGGUGCCCAGGGAGAACCCCUUGGAUAUCGCCAGGAUGAUCCUAGCUAUCGUUCUUUUCACUCUGGUGGAUAUGGCCAGGAUGCCUUGGGUAUGGACCCCAUGAUGGAACAUGAGAUGGGUGGCCACCACCCUGGUGCUGACUAUCCAGUUGAUGGGCUGCCAGAUCUGGGGCAUGCCCAGGACCUCAUGGAUGGGCUGCCUCCAGGUGACAGCAAUCAGCUGGCCUGGUUUGAUACUGACCUGUAAAUCAUCCUUUAGGUAAGAAGUUUUAAAAAGCCAGUUUGGGUAAAAUACUUUUACUCUGCCUACAGAACUUCAGAAAGACUUGGUUGGUAGGGUGGGAGUGGUUUAGGCUAUUUGUAAAUCUGCCACAAAAACAGGUAUAUACUUUGAAAGGAGAUGUCUUGGAACAUUGGAAUGUUCUCAGAUUUCUGGUUGUUAUGUGAUCAUGUGUGGAAGUUAUUAACUUUAAUGUUUUUUGCCACAGCUUUUGCAACUUAAUACUCAAAUGAGUAACAUUUGCUGUUUUAAACAUUAAUAGCAGCCUUUCUCUCUUUAUACAGCUGUAUUGUCUGAACUUGCAUUGUGAUUGGCCUGUAGAGUUGCUGAGAGGGCUCGAGGGGUGGGCUGGUAUCUCAGAAAGUGCCUGACACACUAACCAAGCUGAGUUUCCUAUGGGAACAAUUGAAGUAAACUUUUUGUUCUGGUCCUUUUUGGUCGAGGAGUAACAAUACAAAUGGAUUUUGGGAGUGACUCAAGAAGUGAAGAAUGCACAAGAAUGGAUCACAAGAUGGAAUUUAUCAAACCCUAGCCUUGCUUGUUAAAUUUUUUUUUUUUUUUUUUUAAGAAUAUCUGUAAUGGUACUGACUUUGCUUGCUUUGAAGUAGCUCUUUUUUUUUUUUUUUUUUUUUUUUUGCAGUAACUGUUUUUUAAGUCUCUCGUAGUGUUAAGUUAUAGUGAAUACUGCUACAGCAAUUUCUAAUUUUUAAGAAUUGAGUAAUGGUGUAGAACACUAAUUCAUAAUCACUCUAAUUAAUUGUAAUCUGAAUAAAGUGUAACAAUUGUGUAGCCUUUUUGUAUAAAAUAGACAAAUAGAAAAUGGUCCAAUUAGUUUCCUUUUUAAUAUGCUUAAAAUAAGCAGGUGGAUCUAUUUCAUGUUUUUGAUCAAAAACUAUUUGGGAUAUGUAUGGGUAGGGUAAAUCAGUAAGAGGUGUUAUUUGGAACCUUGUUUUGGACAGUUUACCAGUUGCCUUUUAUCCCAAAGUUGUUGUAACCUGCUGUGAUACGAUGCUUCAAGAGAAAAUGCGGUUAUAAAAAAUGGUUCAGAAUUAAACUUUUAAUUCAUUC